GUAGAAGCGUCCGGGUGGCGGAGGCCGCAGGCCGCAGGAGUGCUGGUGGAGGGGCUUCCAGAAAGACCCUGCGGCAGCGCCCCCCCUCGGCUCUCCCCGCAGGAGAGCGGGCACCUGCGCGGCGCCGGGUGAAGGCGAGAGCCUCGGCGAGCCCUCUGCAGCGGAGCCCCCUGCCCAUUUGGUUUUGGCCAGUCAGCCUGGAAAUCUGCCUGUAGUCAGCUGAUGCAGAGUCACCCUGCAGUUCCUACUUUGAGGGGUUGCAGAAGCACAUAUUUCACUAUGGAGGGCCGCCUGCAGGCCUCGCGCUGACAGGAUCUUUUGUGACGCUGCAAAUGUCCUGAACCACCGGGAGGAACUGGGCCAUUCUAACACCCGUUGCUACCAUGCUGGCCACCCGCCUCUCCAGACCCCUGUCACGGCUCCCAGGAAAAACCCUAAGUGCCUGUGAUAGAGAAAAUGGAGCAAGACGCCCACUAUUGCUUGGUUCUACUUCCUUUAUCCCGAUUGGCCGUCGGACUUAUGCCAGUGCGGCGGAGCCGGUUGGCAGCAAAGCUGUCCUGGUCACAGGCUGUGACUCUGGAUUUGGGUUCUCAUUGGCCAAGCAUCUGCAUUCAAAAGGCUUCCUUGUGUUUGCUGGCUGCUUGAUGAAGGACAAAGGCCAUGAUGGGGUCAAGGAGCUGGACAGCCUAAACAGUGACCGAUUGAGAACCGUCCAGCUCAAUGUCUGCAGCAGCGAAGAGGUGGAGAAAGUGGUGGAGAUUGUCCGCUCGAGCCUGAAGGACCCUGAGAAAGGCAUGUGGGGCCUCGUUAACAAUGCCGGCAUCUCAACGUUCGGGGAGGUGGAGUUCACCAGCCUGGAGACCUACAAGCAGGUGGCAGAAGUGAACCUUUGGGGCACAGUGCGGAUGACGAAAUCCUUUCUCCCCCUCAUCCGAAGGGCCAAAGGCCGCGUCGUCAAUAUCAGCAGCAUGCUGGGCCGCAUGGCCAACCCGGCCCGCUCCCCGUACUGCAUCACCAAGUUCGGGGUAGAGGCUUUCUCGGACUGCCUGCGCUAUGAGAUGUACCCCCUGGGCGUGAAGGUCAGCGUGGUGGAGCCCGGCAACUUCAUCGCUGCCACCAGCCUUUACAGCCCUGAGAGCAUUCAGGCCAUCGCCAAGAAGAUGUGGGAGGAGCUGCCUGAGGUCGUGCGCAAGGACUACGGCAAGAAGUACUUUGAUGAAAAGAUCGCCAAGAUGGAGACCUACUGCAGCAGUGGCUCCACAGACACGUCCCCUGUCAUCGAUGCUGUCACACACGCCCUGACCGCCACCACCCCCUACACCCGCUACCACCCCAUGGACUACUACUGGUGGCUGCGAAUGCAGAUCAUGACCCACUUGCCUGGAGCCAUCUCCGACAUGAUCUACAUCCGCUGAAGAGUCUCGCUGUGGCCUCUGUCAGGGAUCCCUGGUGGAAGGGGAGGGGAGGGAGGAACCCAUAUAGUCAACUCUUGAUUAUCCACGUGUGGAUUAUCCACCAUGCCAGGAAGACCCAUAACUGGUUUUAACACUAACUAGAGGGAAUGACUUCUUUGCAUAGUGAGUGACUUGGGCCUUCACAAACAGGGUGUGGAGUGGCAGGCAGAGGCCUCUAAAUCUCAGGGCAAACAUGGUGAAUCUAUCUCUCCGGAGAUAAUUUCAUACAGAGAUUUUAAGAAAACAUCUUUAUAUUAAAAACAGAUCUCAUUUGAUCCUUAAGCCAGUCUCAUGAAUGAAAAGGACAGGUUUUUUUCUUUUGUAAAUGAAGCAUUUGCAGCUUAAAGAGGAUGCAUGAAAUAACCCUUUUAUCGCUUAUAAAUAGUGCCAGUUAUGUGUUCCUGCCACGGCUGUGGAAAUACUUCACAUUUGCAUUCCAGGACUGUUUUGGAUCCAUUUGCCCGAGAAUCUUCUGACUAACUCUGUGUCCUCAUCUGGGCAGCACACACCAAGUGCCCACUGGUACCUCUGCAUGUCCAUGGUGCUGUGUGACUGGCCAGCCAGCAGCCAGUGACUCAGAGCUGGCUGUAUGGAGGGGGUGGGAAUGUUUCUGGAGAUUUUUGUUUUUCCAGACACAGUCUUGCUCAGUCCCCUAGGCUGGAGUGCAAUGGCACCAUCUCCGCUCACUGCAACCUCCGCCUCCCUGGUUCAAGCGGUUCUCCUGCCUCAGCCUUCCAAGUAGCUGGGGUUAUAGGCACCCACCACCAUGCCGGGCUAAUUUUUGUAUUUUUAGUAGAGAUGGGGUUUCACCAUGUUGGCUAGGCUGGUCCCGAACUCCCGACUUCAAGUGAUCCGCCUGCCUUGGCCUCCCAAAGUGCUGGGAUUACAGGCAUGAGAUUUUUACUUGAGAUUUUUCCAUCCUCUUUUAGGACUCAGGAUAGACUUGUGUGGAGGUGCUCUCUGGCUAAGGGGAUAAGUUGUUACUGGUUUGGGUCUGCUUGGUUUUGCCUUGGGUGGGGCCGGUGUCGAUGGGGCAGGCUUGGCACGAGCAGUGGUGCCAUGGCAGGGCACUGUGGCAUCUCCCCUAGCAGUGGAUUUGGGGUCCCUGCUUGCCUCACGUGGUGCUUACACACAUGUACACACACACACACACACACACACACACACACACCUUACACACAUGUACACACACACACACACACACACACACACACACACACACACACACACACACACACACACACACACACACACACCCCUGUUCUGCAGGGCUUCAGCGUGGCCUUCAUUCCCGCCUCGCCUCGGCCUCUUUUCAAUUAAGAAGUGAUGCCACUUGAGGCAGGGUCUGCAUGAUCACUUCUUGGGUUUCAGUUUGAAAGCUGCCAUCCCUGCGACUGCCCAGGGCCUGUAUGUUGGGACCGAAGCCAAACACCACUGUCCUCCAGGGGGCUUUCGGCCCGGGGCAGGGUCCCCAGUGCCCGCCUUCGAAUCAGACUCCGCGUUUCCGCCUCUCCCUGGGCGGACCUGCCGCUAGAGGGCGCUCCUCCUCCGCAGCCGGCGCCGGCCUCCAGCGCCCCAGACUCCCGCGCUGCCGCCCGAGCCUGAGGUUUCUCACGGCGUUCGGGAUUCGCGCUUCGGAAACCGGGAACAAAGAAGCAAGCAGCACCCUUCAGAAACAGUGUUCUCGCUCUCCUAGCAGCUGGCCCGGGCCCGGAGGCUGGUGCCAGGAGAAGGCAGAAGAGCCCGGGCAGCCGGAGUGGGCUACGGGGUUCAGGCAGUGCCAAGGAAGAAGGGCCUCACAAUGGGCAAUUCAGCUGCCUCCCGGGCCGUUGUCCCCGCUGUCUUCAAACAGGGGUCCCCUGUCCCAGCUGCCCCAGGAGGAGGGGGGGAGGCAGGCAGGGCCGAAACCCUCCAGAGCCCAGAGGGGGACGCUUGGUGGCCGCUGCAGUUACAUAACCAUAGGAUGCUUUUGUACCGUGGACCUUGUUCUAGCAGGAUCCUUUCGGAAUUGCACUUUUACAUGUUGGGCGAAUUUGUGUCCGUGCUGAAGUUUAUUAAAGGAAAAUAGAUGGA